AGUUGUUUCUGUAACAGCAGAAAGUGCACUCACUAGGAGUAGUCAGAAUUCAAAAUGCUCAAGAGAAAGCCAUCCAAUGUUUCAGAGAAGGAGAAACAUCAAAAACCAAAGCGAAGCAGCAGUUUUGGGAAUUUCGAUCGUUUUCGGAAUAAUUCUUUAUCAAAACCAGAUGAUUCAACUGAGGCACAUGAAGGAGAUCCCACAAAUGGAAGUGGAGAACAAAGUAAAACUUCAAAUAAUGGAGGCGGUUUGGGUAAAAAAAUGAGAGCUAUUUCAUGGACAAUGAAGAAAAAAGUGGGUAAAAAGUACAUCAAAGCCCUUUCUGAGGAAAAGGAUGAGGAAGAUGGAGAGAAUGCCCACCCAUAUAGAAACAGUGACCCUGUGAUUGGGACCCACACAGAGAAGGUGUCCCUCAAAGCCAGUGACUCCAUGGAUAGUCUCUACAGUGGACAGAGCUCAUCAAGUGGCAUAACAAGCUGUUCAGAUGGUACAAGUAACCGGGACAGCUUUCGACUGGAUGACGAUGGCCCCUAUUCAGGACCAUUCUGUGGCCGUGCCAGAGUGCAUACGGAUUUCACGCCAAGUCCCUAUGACACUGACUCCCUCAAAAUCAAGAAAGGAGACAUCAUAGACAUUAUUUGCAAAACACCAAUGGGGAUGUGGACAGGAAUGUUGAACAAUAAAGUGGGAAACUUCAAAUUCAUUUAUGUGGAUGUCAUCUCAGAAGAGGAAGCAGCCCCCAAGAAAAUAAAGGCAAACCGAAGGAGUAACAGCAAAAAAUCCAAGACUCUGCAGGAGUUCCUAGAGAGGAUUCAUCUGCAGGAAUACACCUCAACACUUUUGCUCAAUGGUUAUGAGACUCUAGAAGAUUUAAAAGAUAUAAAAGAGAGUCACCUCAUUGAAUUAAAUAUUGAAAACCCAGAUGACAGAAGAAGGUUACUAUCAGCUGCUGAAAACUUCCUUGAAGAAGAAACACACAUCUAGGUAUUUUGCCCAAUUUGCAGAUGAGGCAAAAAUUUGGAGAUGAAUUUCAAAGAAGUCGAACAGCUAGAUGAGUGCAGAGAUGGAGAUUUAAUCAAAGGGAGUCUGCUGUAAAACUCCUCCACAUGUGCAAAUUGGCCAAUAUGAAAGCAAUGAAUAUUUGAAAAUUGAAGUUUUCUGCUACUUCACCAAUUUUCUCAAGGGCUUUGAUUCAGUUUUCUAUAUCAGAAGGUAAAAGGCGAGAGGCUUCCAUGGCUGCCUGUCAACAGGGUUUGUGGAGAGAAGGGGCUGGGAACCUGGGCAAGCAGCACUUUCAGCAAUAAACAGUAUCCUCAGGGGCCCACAGAGGGAAGAUGGUUUCAGUGCCAAAGGCUUGAGUCCCCUUAAUUUUUUCAUUCCACUUCACUCAUCACCUGUCUCCUUUCUAUGCUAGCAAAAGAACAAUUAUUCAUAGAUGGUAAAAUUAUUUAUAGAGCCGAUGUAAUUAAAAAGAAAAAAAAAGAAAAGAAACACCUGAUGCAAAAUUCUUCCAUUGCAAGGUGAGAAGAUGAAAAUCCAAGUAGCUAAGUGGCUUUCUCAAGCUCACAAAUCUAUAAUUCAGUCUCUUACAUCUAUCAGAAACAUGUUCCGCCUUAUCCUGGUCUCUGAAAACAAAACAUAGUGUCUCCAAAGCAUUAAAUGGUUUUUGAUGUUUGAUAUAAAAAAGGACAUGUCCCAGAAAUUAUUCCCCUGCAUAAAACUUUAGAAAAUGAUGCUUGAAGGUCACUAGAAGUUGAUUACUUAAUGACAGCCAGUAAGGUACAAACAUACACAGAGCCAAAUUCUGGGAGAUGAAAAAUGGAAAAAAAAAAUACAGAUUCAACCAGUGCUUCUUGUCAACACACUACUCUGAGAUUUUUCUUAUUUUAAUCUUAUGGUCUAGAGUAGUAUUAGAAUAUACAUGUCAAAAAGAUGCAUAUUGCAGGUUAGGCUAUUCUGACUGAAAGCUAUUUAUCUUUUAUGAAACUGCUUUGCUCAAGAAAUAAAGAAGAAUGACUUCCAUUUGUCAAUAAGAUGUCGAGUUCUGAUGAUUUGGCACCAUACUGGCUGCAUGCUUAUUUUUAUCUAUUUUCUACUCUGUGAAUCAUAUCUCCUACAACCAUGCUAAAGAUUAAACACACAACCUUCCUGUACCUUGAAUGAUAAAGACCUUGAGUAUAUGGUUAUAUAAAACUGAGACAUUUAAAAACAAAUGCAUGUCACGUUAAACGUUAAAAAUAGUUUGCCUUUCUUUUUAAGAAUGGGACAUGUAAAUUUUCUAGGAUAUUAUGGAUGCAUUUUAUUUUGAUCAUUGAAUGAUGUCAGUUUGAGGAAUGGCAAUAAAUUUCUAGUUUGGUGUUUCAUUGUUAGAUUGAGAACAUAAAAGGAUUUGCUUUGCUAAUCAUGCAAUAUAAAAGUUGAGCAAAAUGGGCACAUAUCUUGAGGAUAAGAGCUAAAAUUUUGAGAUAAUGUAGAAAAGACAAGUCCUAUGUGAGUCUUAAAUAUAUCUAGAGAGACCAAGAGGAUGGGGUACAAAACAGGGAAAAAAACCAGACUUCUAAGAUUUAAAGCAAGAAUUUUUCCUUUUCUCUUCUUAGCCCAAGAUAGAUAGCAUUGUACCCACUUUGACCUUGAAAAUGUAAACUGGAUUACACUUUUUUUUUUUUUUGUAUUGUACUUUAAGUUCUGGGAUACACGUGCAGAACAUGGAGGUUUGUUACACAGGUAUACACAUGCCAUGGUGGUUUGCUGCACCCAUCAACCCUUCAUCUACAUUAGGUAUUUCUCCUAAUGCUAUCCUUCCCCUAGCCCCCCACCCCCUGACAAGCAGUGGUGUGUGAUGUUCCCCUCCCUGUGUCCAUGUGUUCUCAUUGUUCAACUCCCACUUGUGAGUGAGAACAUGUGUUUGGUUUUCUGUUCCUGUGUUAGUUUGCUGAGAAUGAUGGUUUCCAGCUUCAUCCAUGUCCCUGUAAAGGACAUAAACUCAUCCUUUUUUAUGGCUGCGUAGUAUUCCAUGGUGUAUAUGUGCCAGAUUUUCUUUAUCCAGUCUGUCAUUGAUGGGCAUUAGGGUUGGUUGCAAUUCUUUGCUAUUGUGAAUGGUGCUGCAAUAAACAUAUGUGUGCAUGUGUCUUUAUAGUAGAGUAAUUUAUAAUCCUUUGGGUAUAGACCCAGUAAUGGGAUUGCUGGGUCAAAUGGUAUUUCUGGUUCUAGAUCUGUGAGGGAUCGCCACACUGUCUUUGACAAUGGUUGAACUAAUUUACAUUCCCACUAACAGUGUAAAAGCAUUCCUAUUUCUCCACAUCCUCUUCAGCAUCUGUUUUUUCUUGACUUUUUAAUGAUCCUGAUUCUAACUGGUGUGAGAUGGUAUCUAGGUCACUGCUUGGUGGGAAGUAAAGAUGCUUCUCCAACAAGCUGAUGAAAGGGCUGGUAUGUGGCGUUAGUGCUGAUCACAGGAUUACCUCUGGAGGAGGAUAACCACCCUGGGGUUCUGCAAUCCCAGCAAGACCAGCAUAGAUAUUUGGAAUUUGCUCCUGUGUUGCAUUUAAACUGAGAGGAAUUAGGUCAUCGGUUCCCUCAACUGGGAAUCUAGAUAAGGUUAUAGGGAGAAGAAAAAUUGGAGUGAGAUGCAGCUCUUGAAGGGACAAGAGAGCAGGAUCUGUUUAUUUUGUGCACAUUUAGGUUUUUCUAUUUAUUAUCUGAAUUUAAAAAUGUUUCAUUUACUUUGGAAGUCAAUAUUCCCAAAUAAAAAAGAGAACAGAAAA